AGUCACUCCCGCUCCCGGCACAAACACACACAGCCGUAGCCCACACUCCUGACACCAGAGGGUUCCUCCCCGUCUCCUGCUGCCCACCCAGCACCUCCACCCAGAAGUCUCAAGCCUUUUGGAGAGUAGCUCGUCACCUCCCCCGAUCCAAAUCCUUGACAGCCCUGCCCUCUUCCUUCUCCACAUCUUGGUAUCUGCCUUUCUCCUAUGCCCUUGACCUGUCAUCUCUCCUGGCCCUGGCAGCACCUCCAACCGGUCACACCCCCUCCACUCCCGGUGCUGAGCCACGUUUUUAAAAUGCAAAUCUGGCAUUGUCACUCCCUACUUAAGCCUUCUGUGGCUUGCCGUGCCCUCGAGGUAAAGCCUGCCCUGGAGCCCAGGCUCAGCCUCGCGGGCUGCCCCUCCUCCGAUCACACUGUGCUGGUCCCUCCUCCUGUUCCUUACCCAUGCGGAGCCCCUAUCUGGAACUCUGCCUACAUUCCUUCCUCGGAGAGACCUACCUUCACCCCAGCCGUACCCUGUCCCACCCUUCAGACCCUCCAUCCCAGCACCCCACUCUAUUUGUCCUCCCUGCUCAAUUCAGAGCUUCAAGAGGGCAGCAGUUGUAUAAGUCUUGCUCCCUGCAUGCGCGAGUGCCUGCCACAGUGUUUGGCACAUAUGUGAGCUUAGUGUGUAUUUGUUGAAUGAAUGAAUGAGAGAGGGAAGAAGGCCCCACUUAGGUGGAGGAAGCAGUCAUUGUCAGGUGCAGUUUCCCUUCUGCAGGAACAAGUGCCUCAUGUAGCCAGCAAACAUUUGGCACCUAUCCAGUGCCAGGUCCUGGAGGCCAAAGCCGAGGAGCCGUCCCCUCCCCCAGCUCUCCUUCAGAGGGAUGGUUGGGGAGGAGGUGCCAAGGCUUUCGGUCUGCCCUCUCAGGGCCACCCAGGCUGGUUUUUCAGUGGGGGCUAGAGGUGCUGGGAGGUGCCCUCCCCUUCUCCCAGGAAGUUCCUGAGGGACAGGGGUCAUGUGACCCCAAGUGUUUUGGGGGGACUGGCCAAGGCCUGGGGCUCUGAGGUUAAAGGACACAUUCUUCAGAUUCCUGAAGGGGGAUGGAGGCAGCUAAAGGUGCCCCCUCCCUAAGACUGGCUUGGGUUGAGGCCUGGGGCACUGGUAGGACUGCUGAGGUGGACAGAGGAGUUGCUGUGACGUUUUCAAGCCCCGCCCCCACUUCUCAAAAACAGCCUUUGGUUACUUGGUGCCCAGGGGUGAGGUGGCCUUUCCUGGAUUUGCACAGUGUGACCUGAGCGUGUGGAUAACUGUGGCCAGUUGAGUGGGGGGUUGUCAGUGCCUGUGUGUGGUGGCAGGAGGGCUGCCUGAUUGUCAGGGCUCAGAUCCCAGAAGAAGCCUGGCUCUCAGAUUCAGGGCCUGUCUCUGGGGUUCCUCGGCGGUGUGGUAUUUCUGUCUGAGCCAGCUCCUGGGAACUGCUUUUCCUUCCUCCAGGACCCUAGGGAGGGGGCUGUGCUCACCCUGGGAACACUGCCAUGGUCAGGAUCUUGAUUCCUGGGUAGCUGCUGAGGGCCCCUCCCCCCACCUCUGACUCACUGUCUGACACUUUUCUUAGAUUCUCACUAUGUUUCAUUCCCUCUUGGCCUCUCCUUGUCUCUGGCUCAGUCUUUUUGUUUCAUCUCCUGCCUCUGCCUCUUAGCCUCUGGAUUCCGAGGUGGAACAGAGGAACAUGAGAACCAGGGGCACUUCCCCCGCCUCUCCAGAGGAGUAUCAGGGAGGAGGUAAUUUCUCAUUUCAUUCCCGCUCUGCAGAUUUGGAGGGGAUUGUUCAUCACUAGAACCUGCAGCAUGACCGUAGCUUCCCUGUGUCUCUGUUUCCCUGUCUGUAGGCUUGGAGGUCAUAACCUCCUCACCUUAAGUUCUCUUUCUGUGGCGAUCCCUUAGGCAGAGCCGCAGUGCGUAUCUGAGCCUGCUUUCCUGACAUCUCUCUCCAUCUGUUUCCUCUUGGGGGACCAGGGAGCCUCCUGGGAUUGCCUACAUUGGCACCUGCCUGCAGCCUGAGCUUCCCUCUCCUGCCACCAGAGCCACCCUUUUUGAGCACCAUUCUUGCUUGUACCCUCUGGCACAGCUGGGGGAUAGACAUGUGACUCUCCUCCUGCCCCUCUUAAAUUAACUGUGACAGGAGCAGGAGAAGGUCACACUGACCAGUCGCCCUCAGCAGCCUCAUGUGGGUAAGAUUGCCUGUGCAGUUGGGUCUAUACCCGAUAUGCAGGGCUGGUCUGCUUACCUCUGGUAUUAUCAGGUGCCUUCUCUAUGCCAGACUCUGUCCUAGACAUGGGCACAUGGGCAGCCAGAGAGAAAUGCCCUCAGUGUGAGGCAGAUGAGCAAUGAGGCCCUUGCAGUCUGAUCAGAUAUAGUCUGUGAUAGGGAAAUACCAGGGUUUUUGGGAGCUGUUUUCCUUUGGGCUGCUAUAAUGGAAAGUCCAUAGACUGGGUUGCUUAAACAAAAGAUUUAUUUUUCACACUUUGGGAGGUUGUGAAGUCCAAGAUCAAGGCUCUAGUCAGCCUGAUGAAGUCUGCCUUCUUGGCUUGCAGAUGGACACCUUCUUGCUGGGUCUGAGCUCACAUGUUGGAGAGGGAGACCAUCUCUUUUGUGUCACUUCUUAUAAAGGUGCUAAUAAGGUGUCAUUCAUCUCCUGAUUACCCCAAGGCCCACCUCCAAAUACCGUCACACUGGGGAUUCAGUCUCAACAUAAGAAUUUUGGUAGGAUACAAAUAUUCAGUCCAUAGCAGGAGCACAGAAAGGCAGGAGGAAGGAGUGGGGGAUUCAGGAAGCCCCUUGAAAGAUGACUUUCUGAAAGGGAAUAAGGCUGGGUUGUUCCAGCUUUGCAGAGGCCAGGAGGUGAGCAGGGACAUGGCCAUUACGGGAACUGCCAGUUCAGCUGGAGUAAAGAGAGCAAGGUGGGGAGAGGGAAGCAGUGGCCAGGUCAGCUUCAGCUUCUUGAAUUCUGGACUUGAUCCUAAUGCCCCAAGGGGAGCUAUAGAGUGGUUCUAGGCGUGGGAGUGGCAGGUAAAUGUGUGGUUUAAGAAGGUCAUUCUGGCUGCAGGAUCAAGAAUGGCUGGGGAAAGAGGGCAGGAGUAGAGGGACAUGGGGUGGCCACUGUGGGGACAGAGACAUGUUAAGGUUAGUGAACUUUUUAAAUUGAUAGUAACCUAAAUAAAAUGCGUAAGUAUAUAAAUCUUAAGUGUCCAUAAGACGAAUUUUUACAAUUUUAGACAUUCAUUUAACCACCAUGCAGAUCAACAUAGAACUUUUACAGGUCCCCCAGCCCUUCCUACCUCCCACCCCAGAAAAUUUCCCUCAUGACUCUCUCCAGGGUGUCCUUCUCCCUCUCCUGGGGAACCACUGCUCUGACUUAUAUCAUCACAGAGUAGUUCUGCCUUUUUUUUUGAACAUUUGCAUGUAUUUCGUGUCUGCCUUCUUUCACUCAGCAUGAUGUCUGUGAGAUGCAUCUGUGUCGUGUGCAUCCAGGAGCUGGAGCUCAUUUUUUUUUUUUUUUUAAACAGUGUGGAAUAACACAUUCACUGAGCACUUAUCACUAAUCUAAGAACAUGUGACAUGUGUUGAUUCUUCUAAACCCCCCAACCCUAUGAGGUCUUAAGACAAAGAAUUGGAGGCACAGAGAGGUUAAGGAACUUGCCCAGGAUUACCCAGCCAAGUAACAGUGGAGCCAGAGUUCAAAAGCAGGCAGUCUGGUUCUGGAGCCGAAGCUCUUAACACUGCCACGUGGCCUCCAUGCAAAAGCAGGCAGUCUGGUCCUGGAGCCGAAGCUCUUAACACGGCCACGUGGCCUCCAUGAUACCUCCUGGGUCUGUUCCUGGCUCUGUGUGGAUUAAACGGAUUUACAUGAACUCCCAGGCAUGGCGUGCCUGGAUAUAGAUGGAGGAAGAGAGAGGAAGGAGUUGAGGAUGACUGCAGGUUUCUGGCUUGAGUGACUGGGUGGGUGGUGGGGCUGUUACUAAGAUAGGGAACACAGGAAGAGGAACAGAUGGCAUGGGGGGUGGGGAACAGACACAAGGGGUUCGAUUUGGGGCCUGCAGAAUUUUAUGUUUCUAGGGGAUGGUUGGGCGGAGAUAACAAGUGGGCAGUGGGUCCUGGGGGAUCUCAGGCUGGAUGUGUGGUGAAGGAGGCAUUCAGGGCCCUGUAGAUGGCAUCUGGAACUGGGGAAAGGAUGGGGUCUCUUGGCAGGAUGCGAUGGGGACAGGAUGUGUGGGUGUUGUUUGUCCAUAUGUGUGUUUCCGUGUUGUCUGAGCAUGUGUGUACAUGUGAGUAUGCCUGCCUCUGGGUCAUGAAUCCCCCACCUCCUGGGAGAACCUGCUGGUCAGCUGGGAGCUGGGUUGUUUUUGUUUGUGGUUUGACCCUGGGAGGGGGGUGCCAAGCCUGAGAAACUACCCACGGAGAAGCCCCCGGAAACAUCUGUGAGUCUUCCCCCAGGCCCAGGGUGGGGGAUUGGCUGGGGAGGGAGAUUUUCUUGCUUCUCUCACGCUUGCCUAGGGGAGGCUGUCCCUGGGGUAAACAUUAUCCAGUUAGUAAGGUUGACAGCAAACUCUACAGGAUUCGGGGACUUUGUAGGCGGCUGGGAAGAGGGCAAAGGAGUGUUUGGAAAGGACACCUGAGUAGAGGAGACCAAGACAGCCUUCUGGUUGGUUUUUCCUGUUCUCUCUCAUUUCCUGUGAUGGCAGUGGGGGAAGGGUUCCCCAGCACUGGGGCCUCGGCCUCAGCUUCAACUUCCUUUCCCUUUCCCCCUGGUGACCUCCCCGAAGGCCCAGCUGGAGCAACAGACACAAGGCUGUCUGUCCCCAGACCCCAGAGCACGUCCGGCACCACCAUGACUGGGCUGUUGAAGAGGAAAUUUGACCAGCUGGAUGAGGACAACUCCUCGGUCUCCUCCUCCUCCUCUUCCUCUGGGUGCCAGUCUCGCUCCUGCUCCCCAAGCUCUUCUGUCUCCCGUGCCUGGGACUCAGAGGAGGAAGGCCCCUGGGAUCAGAUGCCCCUGCCUGACCGUGACUUCUGCGGCCCCAGAAGUUUCACCCCCCUGUCUAUCCUGAAGCGGGCUCGCCGGGAGCGCCCAGGCCGUGUAGCCUUUGAUGGGAUCACCGUCUUCUACUUCCCCCGCUGCCAGGGCUUCACCAGUGUGCCCAGCCGUGGUGGCUGUACUCUGGGUAUGGCCCUUCGCCACAGUGCUUGCCGUCGCUUCUCUUUGGCUGAGUUUGCGCAGGAGCAAGCCCGUGCACGGCACGAGAAGCUCCGCCAGCGCUUGAAAGAGGAGAAGUUGGAGAUGCUGCAGUGGAAGCUUUCGGCAGCUGGGGUACCCCAGGCAGAGGCAGGGCUGCCACCUGUGGUGGAUGCCAUUGAUGACGCCUCUGUGGAGGAGGACUUGGCAGUCGCUGUGGCAGGUGGCCGGUUGGAAGAAGUGAGCUUCCUACAGCCCUACCCAGCCCGGCGACGUCGAGCUCUGCUGAGGGCUUCAGGUGUGCGAAGGAUCGAUCGGGAGGAGAAGCGGGAGCUGCAGGCACUGCGCCAAUCCCGGGAGGAUUGUGGCUGUCACUGCGAUAGGAUCUGCGACCCUGAGACCUGCAGCUGCAGCCUGGCAGGCAUCAAGUGCCAGAUGGACCACACAGCAUUCCCCUGUGGCUGCUGCAGGGAGGGCUGUGAGAACCCCAUGGGCCGUGUGGAAUUUAAUCAGGCAAGAGUUCAGACCCAUUUCAUCCACACACUCACCCGCCUGCAGUUGGAACAGGAGGCUGAGAGCUUUAGGGAGCUGGAGGCCCCUGCCCAGGGCAGCCCACCCAGCCCUGGUGAGGAGGCCCUGGUCCCUACUUUCCCACUGGCCAAGCCCCCCAUGAACAAUGAGCUGGGAGACAACAGCUGCAGCAGCGACAUGACUGAUUCUUCUACAGCAUCUUCAUCAGCAUCGGGCACUAGUGAGGCUCCUGACUGCCCCACCCACCCAGGCCUGCCUGGCCCUGGCUUCCAGCCUGGCGUUGAUGAUGACAGCCUGGCACGCAUCUUGAGUUUCAGUGACUCUGACUUCGGUGGGGAGGAGGAGGAAGAGGAGGAAGGGAGCGUGGGGAACCUGGACAACCUCAGCUGCUUCCAUCCAGCUGACAUCUUUGGUACUAGUGACCCUGGUGGCCUGGCCAGCUGGACCCACAGCUAUUCUGGCUGUAGCUUCACAUCAGGCGUCCUGGAUGAGAAUGCCAACCUGGAUGCCAGCUGCUUCCUAAAUGGUGGCCUUGAAGGGUCAAGGGAAGGCAGCCUUCCUGGCACCUCAGUGCCACCCAGCAUGGACGCUGGCCGGAGUAGCUCAGUGGAUCUCAGCUUGUCUUCUUGUGACUCCUUUGAGUUACUCCAGGCUCUGCCAGAUUAUAGUCUGGGGCCUCACUACACAUCACAGAAGGUGUCUGACAGCCUGGACAACAUCGAGGCACCUCACUUCCCCCUGCCUGGCCUGUCUCCACCUGGGGAUGCCAGCAGUUGCUUCCUGGAGUCCCUCAUGGGCUUCUCCGAGCCAGCCGCCGAAGCCCUAGAUCCCUUUAUUGACAGCCAGUUUGAGGACACUGUCCCAGCAUCUCUAAUGGAGCCUGUGCCGGUGUGAGGACCAGGAUGUCUUUUCCCAGCCCCAAGAGACCUGUUGCUGCUUUCUUGUAAUUAUGGGGCUCCCCAGAGUCUGCGUAACAGUCUCCCACUGGCUGGCUCACCCACAGGUGCCAUGUGCACACUCCUGGUUUUCAAACAAUUCUCUGGAUUUAUUUAUUUGUUUUAACUUUUCUGUGCUGAAGAGAGGACUGGGGGGAGGGGGCUUCCCCUUUCAGCUGCCCGGCCCCCCACACCCACAGCUUGCUCUUCUAUCUCCACAACGUGAGCCUGGAAGAGGAGAAAAUGUGGCUCCUCUGGAGCUUGGCAGACCACUUUUCGGUCUUUGCGUGAUGUUCCUUAGCCCAAAGACGGUGAGACAGGGCUGAAAUCAGGUGGCUUCUGCCACCCUGAGCCCUAGACCCAUGGGUGGCUAAAUCCACUGGACUGUGAAGACUAUAAUUUAUUUCCAUAAUUUAUUUGGAGAUUGAGGAGGCUUUGGUUGCACUUCUUUGGCUGGUGGGUAAUGCCAGGGGUGGGGUGGGCACAGGCCCUCAAGAGCCCCUUUUGCCUUGUAGUCCUACACCUUGCCCUGCCUGGGCUUUGGUGCAGACUAGGUGUGGAUUUGAGCUCUGUGAUCUAUGUCUGCUGCCUGGCUCCUAGAUGGCUCUGUGGGCAGGUGCUGGCCAAGGACAUCAUCUAGGCAGGGGGAGAGCCUGGGCUGAACAGCUGUGACCAAAACUCCCUUCUGCCCCACCCUGCCCCCUCCACUUCCUGCCCUCUGUUCCAUCUUCCCCCUUCCCAAAGGCCACAGCCUUUAUUCCAGGCCCAGGGAUGUAGGAGGGGGAAGGAGGAAACAGGAAGCCCAGAGAGGGCAAAGGGCCUACCUCGGGGCGCGAACCAUGCCCCAGACUAUUAUCUCAGGGCUUUCUGGGCACUGCACUUCAGCGUGGCCCACCUGCCCAUGCCCUGAGGCCAGUUGGCGAGGGGUGGCUCCUGAGGGUUUUUAUACCCUUUGUUUGCUAAUGUUUAAUUUUGCAUCAUAAUUUCUACAUUGUCCCUGAGUGUCAGAACUAUAAUUUAUUCCAUUUCUCUCUGUGUCUGUGCCAAGAAACGCAGGCUCUGGGCCUGCCCCUUGCCCAGGAGGCCUUGCCAGCCUGUGUGCUUGUGGGAACACCUUGUACCUGAGCUUACAGGUACCAAUAAAGAGGCUUUAUUUUUA